GGAGGCGGCGUUGCCGGGCUCUCCGGAAGGAGACGUGGCGGCGGUUGGGCCGGUGAUACCCGGGCGCUUUAUAGUCCCGCCGCCUCCUCCUCCACCUCCUCCUCCUCCUCCUCUCCUCCUGGAGCAGAGGAGGUUGUGGCGGUGGCUGGAGAAAGCGGCGGCGGAGGAUGGAGGAAGGAGGCGGCGGCGUACGGAGUCUGGUCCCGGGCGGGCCGGUGUUACUGGUCCUCUGCGGCCUCCUGGAGGCGUCCGGCGGCGGCCGAGCCCUUCCUCAACUCAGCGAUGACAUCCCUUUCCGAGUCAACUGGCCCGGCACCGAGUUCUCUCUGCCCACAACUGGAGUUUUAUAUAAAGAAGAUAAUUAUGUCAUCAUGACAACUGCACAUAAAGAAAAAUAUAAAUGCAUACUUCCCCUUGUGACAAGUGGGGAUGAGGAAGAAGAAAAGGAUUAUAAAGGCCCUAAUCCAAGAGAGCUUUUGGAGCCACUAUUUAAACAAAGCAGUUGUUCCUACAGAAUUGAGUCUUAUUGGACUUACGAAGUAUGUCAUGGAAAACACAUUCGGCAGUACCAUGAAGAGAAAGAAACUGGUCAGAAAAUAAAUAUUCACGAGUACUACCUUGGGAAUAUGUUGGCCAAGAACCUUCUAUUUGAAAAAGAACGAGAAGCAGAAGAAAAGGAAAAAUCAAAUGAGAUUCCCACUAAAAAUAUCGAAGGUCAGAUGACACCAUACUAUCCUGUGGGAAUGGGAAAUGGUACACCUUGUAGUUUGAAACAGAACCGGCCCAGAUCAAGUACUGUGAUGUACAUAUGUCAUCCUGAAUCUAAGCAUGAAAUUCUUUCAGUAGCUGAAGUUACAACUUGUGAAUAUGAAGUUGUCAUUUUGACACCACUCUUGUGCAGUCAUCCUAAAUAUAGGUUCAGAGCAUCUCCUGUGAAUGACAUAUUUUGUCAAUCACUGCCAGGAUCUCCAUUUAAGCCCCUCACCCUGAGGCAGCUGGAGCAGCAGGAAGAAAUACUAAGGGUGCCUUUUAGGAGAAAUAAAGAGGAAGAUUUGCAAUCAACUAAAGAAGAGAGAUUUCCAGCGAUCCACAAGUCGAUUGCUAUUGGCUCUCAGCCAGUGCUCACUGUUGGGACAACCCACAUAUCCAAAUUGACAGAUGACCAACUCAUAAAAGAGUUUCUUAGUGGUUCUUACUGCUUUCGUGGGGGUGUCGGUUGGUGGAAAUAUGAAUUCUGCUAUGGCAAACAUGUACAUCAAUACCAUGAGGACAAGGAUAGUGGGAAAACCUCUGUGGUUGUCGGGACAUGGAACCAAGAAGAGCAUAUUGAAUGGGCUAAGAAGAAUACUGCUAGAGCUUAUCAUCUUCAAGACGAUGGUACCCAGACAGUCAGGAUGGUGUCACAUUUUUAUGGAAAUGGAGAUAUUUGUGAUAUAACUGACAAACCAAGACAGGUGACUGUAAAACUAAAGUGCAAAGAAUCAGAUUCACCUCAUGCUGUUACUGUAUAUAUGCUAGAGCCUCACUCCUGUCAAUAUAUUCUUGGGGUUGAAUCUCCAGUGAUCUGUAAAAUCUUAGAUACAGCAGAUGAAAAUGGACUUCUUUCUCUCCCCAACUAAAGGAUAUUAAAGUUAGGGGAAAGAAAAGAUCAUUGAAAGUCAUGAUAAUUUCUGUCCCACUGUGUCUCAUUAUAGAGUUCUCAGCCAUUGGACCUCUUCUAAAGGAUGGUAUAAAAUGACUCUCAACCACUUUGUGAAUACAUAUGUGUAUAUAAGAGGUUAUUGAUAAACUUCUGAGGCAGACAUUUGUCUCGCUUUUUUUCAUUUUUGUUGUGUCUUAUAAACUGACUGUUUUUCUUUGCUUGGAUACUGUGAUUCCAAAAUAAAUCUCAUCCAAGCAAGUUAGAGUCCAGCCUAAUCAAAUGUCAUAAUUGUUGUACCUAUUGAAAGUUUUUAAAUAAUAGAUUUAUUAUGUAAAUUAUAGUAUAUGUAAGUAGCUAAUGAAGUAAAGAUCAUGAAGAAAGAAAUUGAUAGGUGUAAAUGAGAGACCAUGUAAAAUAUGUAAAUUCUAGUACCUGAAAUCCUUUCAACAGAUUUUUAUAUAGCAACUGCUCUCUGCAAGUAGUUAAACUAGAAACUGGGCACAUGGUAGAGGCUCACAUGGGAGUUGUCCUCACCCUUGUUAAUCUCAAGAAACUCUUAUUUAUAAUAGGUUGCUUCUCUCUCAGAACUUUUAUCUAUUACUUUUUUCUUCUUAUGAGUAUGUUUACUCUCAGAGUAUCUAUCUGAUGUAGACAGUUGGUGAUGCUUCUGAGACUCAGAAUGGUUUACUCUAACAAAACACUGUGCUGUCUAUCCCUUGUACUUGCCUACUGUAAUAUGGAUUUCACUUCUGAACAGUUUACAGCACAAUAUUUAUUUUAAAGUGAAUAAAAUGUCCACAAGCA